AUUUCACUUGGAGGAAAGAGAGAAGGAAGGAAGCUGAGGACUUAGCAGGGUAAGUUUUUUUUUCCGUCAACCUGUCUGCUUGCUUAGUUUAUAAUUGAGUAAAGUAUUUAUCACCCCAGGCAGUGUUAAUCACUGAUUAAACAGCUGAAUGUGGCCAUAAUUACAGUGUCCUUAAUGUAUUUCUCCUUCUCUUUUCCUACCCCCUUAUAAGGAUCUCCAAUGACCAGUUUCAGUCUUCCUUCUCCCUACCUCUCCAAAGACGUUUUGCAUUUUUUGGUGACUUACAGAAAAUUAGAUGAGCACUCCUUAUCUGGAGAUAGUGAAAAUAUGACUGUAGUUUAGGUGAAACUUGGGACUCUUGGUGGUAAAGAAGAAGAUGGGAAACCUAGGUCUAGGAAUAGAUUAAUAUUUUGUCUUGAAUUUGGACAUGAAGGAUAAAAGUUUUUCUAGGCAAUCAAGAUCAUGUCUCCUCUCCAGUUCUUGGUGUUGGUGUUCUCUCUCUUAUACUGGGACUAAAUUAGAGCCUAAGUCACUGGGGAUGGCUAGAAAAAAAUGAAAGGGAUUCCCUUUCUAAGUGGAGAGCAUUCUAGACUCUGGAAAGUUCAAAGAGCUUACUGCAAUUCUUUCCAGCUUCUCCUGUGAGUCCCCUGUUUUUUCCUUUGUUUCUCUCAGUUUAUAACCUGUGAACAGGGAGUAGCCUGGGGCUCUUUACAGGAGAUUUAGAACCAGGGAAGCUGUGUCUGGGCCUGGGGUAUAUAAACUCAAACAUGAACCUGAUGAUGUAUAUAGAUGCAGAUCAAAGACCUGGCUUCUCACCCACCUUCUUUCUUUUCUGCCAGAAAGCUAACUCAUUUGUAUCAUGAACAUUGUGCUCUAGACACAGAGGAGACUGUGACAUUAGGGAUUUUUACCACCACUCCUCUUCCUCAAACUGUGUGAUCCUUUUGCUUUCUGACCAGUUCAGCCAACUCCCAGAUUGCCAAGAGCUAAUCUUCCUUUAGAGGAAGACCUCACCUUGGAAAUGCGGAAAAGUAAAGCAGUACCUUUCUGACCUUAAGUGGCUUGCUUCCAUUGCAGCAAAAAGGCUUAUGUUUUAACUUCAGGGAGAUAUCUAUUAUAAAUUCUGGGAUUUAAGACCCUAGAGUUGUCUCAAAUCACACUUUCCUUCCAUACCUAUUUAAAAAAAAAAAAGUCAUUCUUUCAAGGUUUAAGAAAGUGGUGUCUUGGCCGGGCGCCGUGGCUCAUGCCUGUAAUCCCAGCACUUUGGGAGGUCGAGGUGGGUGGAUCACGAGGUCAGGAGUUCGAGACCAGCCUGACCAACAUGGUGAAACCCCAUCUCUACUAAAAAUACAAAAAUUAGCUGGGCAUGGUGGCGCGAGCCUGUAAUCCCAGCUACUCAGGAGGCUGAGGCAGGAGAAUCACUUGAACCCGGGAGGUGGAGGUUGCAGUGAGCCAAGAUCGCACCACUGCACUCCAGCCUGGGUGACAGAGUGAGACUCUGUCUCAAAGAAAGAAAGAAAAAGAAAAUGUUAUCUUGCCUGAGGCAGGUGGGUAGAGUAGAUAAAUGCUUUUUGUAGAAUGGCAGUGAUUCUGAAAAUGCAAUGAGAAUGUGAGGUGAUUAAAAGUGGAGGACAGAAUGAGGUUAGUUGUUGGAAAUUGGGCCCUAAAGUGUGAAGGGCAAUUCCAUUUACUCUUUUGGUAAAAGGACAUGACCCUUAAACCCUAAGAUAAUCUAAUAUCAUUAGGUCCAAUUUCUUCAUUGAAGGUAAUAUAUAGGAUAUGGUAUACAGAUGAGCUUGACUAUUUCUGUUCUGUGGACUGAAACCAUCCAUUCACCCAUGGGAUAAGGGGAGACAUUAAGAGGGUGGAUGGAAACAUAAGGAUGAGGAGAUAGAAAGUACAAAGGAAAAUACAAAUUUGUUCCUCCAUUAACCUGAGGACAGGUUUUUAAGAGUCAUGUUGUAAGAUAUGGAUAUGAGCUGGAUAAUUCUGGGAGCUUUUUGUUUAUUUUUGCCACCUGCAUACACCUCAGCUGCAUGAUGAUUCUGAGGUUUUUCCUAACAGAUCUGAUCUAGAAGGAUCAAAUGUCAGAUCAUUUUUGUAACAAAACAUGAUCCCUGGUUUGAACUUUAACAGUUUCCUCAUUCACACUGCCAGCGUUUUUAAUCCUCUGUUAUUUCUCUGUACCUGAAGACAAUCUGGGGAUUAAUAACUUUUUAGCCUCUCAAUCUCUAUGAAUACCUUCCUUCCUUUCUUUUUUAAUCGAAGUGAAAAUCAUAUAACAUAAAAUUAAUAAUUUUAAAGUGAGCAAUUAAAUGGCAUUUAGUGUAUUCACGGUAUUGUUCAACCAUCAAUUUUGUCUUGUUCCAAAACAUUUUUAUCACCCCAAAAGAAGACCCCAUAACCAUUAAGCAGUUACUCCCCAUUUUCCCUUCCACCCAGCCCUUAGCAACUACCAAUCUGCUUUCUGUCUCUGGGUUUACCUAUUCUGGAUAUUUCAUAGAAAUGGCAUCAUACAACAUGUAUACAACAUUUUGUGUCUGGCUUUCUUCACUUAGUAUAAUGUUUUUUGAAGUUCCUCUACAUUGUAGCGUGUAUCAGUAUUUCAUUUCUUUUUAUAGCUGAAUAAUAUACAUCUUCAUAUGUAUAUUUAUAUCCCAAUUUGUUUAUCCAUUUAUCCAUUGAUGGACCUUUGGGUUGUUUCUACCUUUUAGCUGUUGCGAAUAGUGCUGCUAUGAACAUUCACAUAUAAGUAUUUGUUUGAGUAUCUGUUUUUAAAUAUUUUGGGCACAUACCUAAGAAUGAAAUUUCUGGUUAUAUAGUAAUAUUAUGUUAACUUUUUGGGGAACUGCCGUACUGUUUUCUAUGGUGGUGGCACCAUUUUACAUUCUCACCUGCAGUGUACGAGGGUUCAAAUUACUCCAUAUCCUCAUCAACACUUGUCAUUUUCUGUUUUUUUUUUUUAUAAUAGCCAUACUAGUGGGUAUGAAGUAAUAUCUCACUGUGGUUCUGAUUUGCAUUUUCCUAAUGACUAUUGAGCAUAUUUUCUUGUGUUUAUUGUCCAUUUGCAUAUAUUCUUUGGGAAAAUGCCUAUUCACAUGUUAUGCCCAAUUUUUUAGUUGGGUUGUUUGGUGGUUUUUUUGUUUGUUAUUGAGUUGUGGGAAUUCUUUAUAUAUUUUGAAUACUAACCCCUUAUCAGAUAUAUGGUGUGCAAAUAUUUUCUUCCAUUCUUGGGGUGUCAUUUGACUCUGUUGUUAGUUUAGCAUCCUUUGAUGCACAAAAGUUUUUAAUUUUGCUGUCCAAUUUAUCUAUUUUGGUGGUGGUGGUGUUGCCUGUGCUUUUGGUGUCAUAUCCUAGAAAUUAUUGCCAAACCUAUGUCAUGAACCUUUCCCCAUAGACUUUUAUAGUUUUACUUCUUAAGUUUAGGUCUUUAUACUUUAAACAUUCAAACUCGAGUCAUUCUAUUUCAUUAAUUUGCAGAAUGUUUCUGUCUAUAUUUCUGUGUUUAUUCUCUCCUCUGUGCUUAGAAUUUAUUUUUUCCCUAUUUCCAAGUAUUCAAAGUAUUCCCAUCUUUCAAGGUCUAUUCCAACUGCCACCUGCUUCAUGAAGAAAGCCACUGAAGAGAUUCUCGCCCACUGAAGAGAUUUUCUUCUUCUGAUCUCCCAUUAGUGCUUUAGUUGCACUUUUCUGGUUGGAUUUAUAUAGUACCUUAUAGUCUACAUCUAAUCUCCCUGCAAGACAUUUAGAUAUAUAUUUCUCAUAUUUGCUUCUAUAUAUAGUGUUUCGCAAAUGAUUUCAUCUGUUUAUCAGUAAAUAUAUAUUACAUGAAUGGACAUUUUAAUUUUUCUCAUAUGGUCCUUUCUGUUUACUCAGCUCUUAUGGAAGGCAUGGCAGAAGAUGAGACAGGGAAAGAGGACAGCACAGAGUCACAGCCAGAUCGUGACUGAGUGUAGGCUUACUUCUACCUCAAAACUUACCACUUUAGGAAAUUUUUCUGACUUGCUUGACUACAUAACUCUUAGUGCACGUUUUGUAUUACAUUUAAUUUUUACUUCUUGGCUUAUUGCUUAUACAUGUGAUAAUAGGUCUUUCAAAAUAAAUGUUUUAUCUCUCUAUAUUAAACUGUCUAACUCUCCAAUUGGAUGGUCACUUUGGAGAAUUAAAACUUCUAUUGCUUUUUCUUCUUUUAAAUUGAGUUUUAAAAUACAUUAAAGCUAUAUUAAUAUUUUCUCCUUAUUAAAAAAGUCAAACAUUACAGGUAAGUAUACAGUUCCAUUUGAUCAGCCCAGUUCCUAUUUAACUGCCUUCUUAAACUAUUCAGAGUUAAUCACUGUUACCAGUUUUCUUUUUUUUUUGAGACAGAGUUUUGCUCUUGUUGCCCAGGCUGGAGUGCAAUGGUGCGAUCUCGGCUCACCGCAACCUCCGCCUCCUGGGUUCAAGCAGUUCUCCUGCCUCAGCCUCCCAAGUAGCUGGGAUUAUAGGCACCCACCACCACGUCCAGCUAAUUUUUUGUAUUUUUAGUACAGAUGGGGUUUCACCAUGUUGGCCAGGCUGGUCUUGAACUCCUGACCUCAGGUGAUCCGCCCGCCUCAGCCUCCCAAAGUGCUGGGAUUACAGGCGUGAGCCACCACGCCCAGCUGUUACCAGUUUUCUAUGGGCCCUGCCAAAUCUUUUUUGAUGCAUUUACUUAUAUAUAUAUAUGUGUGUGUAUAUAUAUAUAUAAUGUAUAGGACUUACUAUGUGUAAAUUAUAUUCAUAUAAAAUUACUUCUUCUUGGCUGGGUGCGGUGGCUCAAGCCUGUAAUCCUGGCAUUUUGGGAGGCCAAGGUGGGUGGAUCACCUGAGGUCAGGAGUUUGAGACCAGCCUGACCAACAUGGUGAAACCCCAUCUCUACUAAAAAAUACAAAAAUUAGCCGGGCCUGGUGGCGCCUGCCCGUAGUCCCAGCUACUCGGGAGGCUGAGGCAGGAGAAUCGCUUGAACCUAGGAGGUGGAGUGAGCUGAGAUUAUGCUGCUGUACUCCAGCCUGGGCGGCAGAGCAAGACUCUGUCUCAAAAAACAACAACAACAACAAAUUACUUCUUCCCUAUUUUCCACAGCUGCCUAUGGUGAUCAAUAACCAGUAAAUACUGAAUAAAUCUUACUGAUAACCUGGGUCUGAGAGACUGGAAUGAGAAAUGAAAGGUCAAGCAUAUGAAAAUACUUCACAAGUGUCCAGCUUGUAAAAUUCCAUUCCAUGUCUAUUCUGCAUAUAAUCUCCAGGUAUCACUGGACAGGCCAUGGCUCCACGGUCCCGGCGACGAAGGCACAAGAAACCUCCCUCAUCAGUGGCUCCCAUCAUCAUGGCCCCAACCACAAUUGUGACCCCUGUGCCUCUGACCCCCUCAAAACCUGGCCCUAGCAUUGACACACUUGGCUUCUUCUCCUUGGAUGAUAAUGUUCCUGGCCUAUCGCAGCUGAUCCUUCAAAAGCUGAACAUGAAAAGCUAUGAAGAAUAUAAGUUGGUGGUAGAUGGGGGUACCCCCGUAUCAGGCUUUGGAUUUCGAUGUCCUCAAGAAAUGUUCCAGAGGAUGGAAGACACAUUUCGAUUCUGUGCUCACUGUAGAGCACUCCCUAGUGGGCUUUCAGACUCCAAGGUUCUCCGGCACUGUAAGAGGUGCAGAAAUGUCUAUUACUGUGGUCCAGAGUGCCAGAAGUCAGACUGGCCCGCACACAGGAGGGUUUGUCAAGAGCUUCGUCUUGUGGCUGUGGACCGUCUCAUGGAAUGGCUUCUGGUCACAGGUGAUUUUGUUCUACCCUCAGGACCUUGGCCAUGGCCACCUGAAGCUGUACAGGACUGGGACUCCUGGUUUUCUAUGAAGGGGUUACACCUAGAUGCUACAUUGGAUGCUGUGCUAGUUAGUCAUGCUGUGACCACCUUAUGGGCCAGUGUAGGACGGCCAAGGCCAGACCCGGAUGUCCUGCAGGGAUCUUUGAAGCGGCUGCUGACAGAUGUCCUGUCACGGCCCUUGACUCUAGGCCUAGGACUUAGGGCCUUGGGGAUAGAUGUUAGGAGGACUGGGGGAAGCACAGUGCAUGUGGUUGGUGCUUCCCAUGUGGAGACAUUUCUUACUCGCCCAGGGGACUAUGAUGAGCUUGGUUACAUGUUUCCUGGGCACCUUGGACUCCGUGUGGUCAUGGUGGGUGUAGAUGUAGCUACUGGCUUUUCACAGAGCACCUCAACUUCACCCCUGGAACCUGGCACAAUUCAGCUUAGUGCCCACAGGGGCCUCUACCAUGACUUCUGGGAGGAGCAAGUAGAGACCGGGCAGACACACCAUCCAGAUUUGGUGGCGGCAUUCCAUCCAGGUUUUCAUUCCUCCCCAGACUUGAUGGAGGCUUGGCUGCCCACCCUGCUGCUACUUCGUGACUAUAAGAUUCCUACAUUGAUUACUGUUUACAGCCAUCAGGAGUUGGUAUCCUCUUUGCAGAUUCUGGUGGAACUGGAUACACACAUCACUGCCUUUGGGUCUAAUCCUUUCAUGUCCCUCAAACCUGAACAGGUCUAUUCCAGUCCCAACAAGCAGCCAGUAUACUGCAGUGCAUACUAUAUCAUGUUUCUUGGAAGCUCCUGUCAGCUGGAUAAUAGGCAAUUAGAAGAGAAAGUGGACGGCGGGAUUUAAAUAGAUCAUAACUGGACAUCUGGAAAACGGGGAGUUUGUGAUGAAAUUACCCUGCUAAUGCCAGGUUCUUGCAAACUUUGAAAAACAUUAUAUUCUAAACCUCAUUUACUGUUUGGGUAAAAAUUCUAAGCUGAAUGAGAGUUUCUGUAUAACAUAACUGGUUUCUUUCUUUUUUUGAGAUGGAGUCUUGCUCUGUUGCCCAGGCUGGAGUGCAGCGGCAUGAUCUCGACUCACUGCAGCCUCCGCCUCCUGGGUUCAAGUGGUUCUCCUGCCUCAGCCUCCCUAGUAGCUGGGAUUACAGGUGCACACCACCACACCUGGCUAAUUUUUGUAUUUUUAGCAGACAGGGUUUCACCAUGUUGGCCAGGCUCGUAUCAAACCCUUGACCCCAGGUGAUCUGCCUGCCUCAGCCUCCCAAAGUUCUGGGAUUACAGGCAUGAGCCACCAUGCCCAGCCAAUGUAACUGGUUUCUAAGAGUUUAGCCACAGUAGCUUCUAGAGAUAGGAAAUUAGAUUUAGUGGGUGGGAAGAGGCCCUGAUGCUGGUCUUUCCAGAGCUUAUAGUUGCUAACACUUUUCUUUGUAAAGAAGUUUACCUUUUGACUGGAACCAGAUGGCACUGAGAAAAAGAAUGAGAACCACCUUAUUCUUCUGAAAAAGACUUUCUUCUCAUCCAGUAAUUUGGGCUAAAAAAUGGAAAGAUGUUGAUGACUUGAAGUGAUGCAAGAAUGGACAAGUCAGGGAAGUCAUUGGGAACAUGGAUGAGGUUGUAAGCAUUGGUACAGUGUCCUGUUUCCUGACUUUUUUGAGAGAAAUGUCUACUUUUCCUGUUUUCUCUUGGGGACUUUUGACCCUAGAGUAGCCCUGGUGUUAUAUUUUAGAUAUCCCAAGCUAUAUCAGACUUUACCUGAAUAUACUGGAGUUACUUAUUAUCCCCCAUUCUAUACCCCAAUAAACUCAGUUUGGGGCUUCUUAA